GUGUUGCCUGAUACUGUGGCACUGUGGGACUAGGCUCUUCACAUUCUACAACUUACCUUUGAGGCUAGACAGUGACAGCUGCCUCUGGCUAUCAUUUUUGUCCUUAAUUGUGAACCGGAAUUUUUCUAGCCAUCCAGGAGAAUCUUUGAAAAAGUUGGAUAUUUUUUGUUUGAAAAGGUAAUUGUACAAUGAGGAUUUUCAUCGCCUUUGAAGGAUCUUUUGAACCGUUUGAUGUUUCAGCAGAUGAAACUGUGGAGGUUGUCAAGCUGAUGAUAAAGGAUUAUUUCCACAUUCCUCUCUCUGAAGACAAACAAGGCAGGCGGUAUCUGGAGUUAAUGUAUGCUGGAGCUGCUCUAAAGGACAGUUGGAGUCUUGCUGAUGUUGGAAUAUCUUUCUGUUCAACUCUCAAAUGCUUUGUUAAGGAAGAAGACAAGCCUACUCUAUACGUGUUCAAUGCUGUAACUCAAGACACAAUGCCAGUAAUGGAGAGCAUUUCCCUUCUUGAUAAAACAGUGUCUGAUCUGAGAACACUGGUAACUCUGAGAUGUGGCCUCCCCGUGAGUGUCUACUGUCUCCGAACCCCAAGGGGCCUGGAGAUGUAUGAUUGCAACACCCUCAAGGACUACCAGACUGAUAUUGGCACAACACUUCGCUUGGAUGUCUGGGAUGGAUGGAAGGAAUUUCUGAUGGGUUGUCUCCUUGGACAAAAACUUAAAGUCCAACGCUACUUAUCAAAAGAAGGACCAGUACUCAAGUAUCAGAAAAGGGUAGCCCUGUACAUUGCUGCUUUUUGUGGGUACAUUGAACUCACUGAAUGGGCCCUGAAGCAGGGUGCGCGGCCCCACGAGGCAGUCGGUGUUCACCCCUAUCGAGCAUGGUGCCAUGAAGCCCUUCAUGCAGAUGUCUCUAAAUGCCCCAUUCAUGCAGCCGCAGAAGCAGGCCAACUGUUGAUUCUGAAGGCCUUUGUCAACUACAGUGUGCUGUGCCUGGAAUGCAAAAAUGCAGCAGGACAAACUCCCCUGACCAUUGUGUUCAAACACAAGCAUAAAGACUGUGUAUUAUAUUUGCUCAGUAAAAUGUGGUCCACAGUUUCUUUUCCAAAAAUUUCAGUCCCAAUGAGGAUUUAUAUUAAAAUAAAACAAUGGAUCCUCAGAGCUCAGAGUCACAGUCUUCAUAAAAGCCAGUUUUGUGGAGCAAGGGUCUUUGGGGCAAAAGUUGGAGACACUGUGAUGGUGGAUGGUUUCACCAAACCAAAAAUGACCUCCAAGAGCUGGCAUAAGGCUGGGAACAGCGACUCACAAAGCAUCGUGCUCAAGCUACCAUCUCUCAGCAAACAAACUGCAAGCAGCAAACCUGUCAAUCCUUUGGCAAUUUCACAGCCGGACACAAGAAAACAAGCCCUCAAAUUUCAUCCACUGGUGAAUGCAAGUUCAUUCUCUGAAUUACAAAAACAUCAACAACAAAAUCAGAAAAAAAUUACUGCCACAGCUAGGAAAAAAGAAAAGCUCAUAAAAAACACAUAUCUUCCCCAAGUCCCCCUCCCUCCAGUUUCAAGAGUGGGAUAUUCACAUCCAUCGUUUUUCUAUGCAACACCCAGUGCUGACUUUUUACUGAAGUCCUCCUUCUCAUCUUUCUUAGAGCACAGUGGGAAGACUCCAUGGGAGAACGCAAUCUACUGCUUAGCUGUGGCAAGGUAAUGUUCUCCCCUUAAACAUACAAACAGCAAAGCUUUUAUAAGGCAGGUCCAGGAUAAGGAAUGGUCCAUAAUGCCCUACUAUGCCACUGAAAGUAAUACAAGUUGUUCCAGUGCAUCAAUACCCAGCUUCAAGGACCUCAUCUUAGCCUCAUCACUAGGACAAAAUGAAUUAAUAUUAUUGGCCAAUCCAAUCUGUGCAGUACUUUACUCCUCAAACUUUCAGGAGGGAAAGAAACACAGUAGAAAGAAUUGUAUCAAUUCUCAAGGUCCCUUGCUGCUGCUGCUGCUGCUGCUGCUGCUGCUGCUGCUGCUGCUGCUGCUGCUGCUGCUGCUGCUUUUCUUUUUUCUUUUUGUUUGAGACAGGGUCUCGUUCUGUUGCUCAGGCUGGAGUGCAGUGGUGCUAUCACAGCUCAUUGCAUUCUUGAAUUCCUAGGCUCAAGCAAUUCUCCCAUCUCAGCCUUCCAAGUAGCUGGGACUACAGGCACAUGCCACUAUAUCUGAUUGAUUUUUUUUUUCUGUAGAGAUG